CUCUUCCUGUCUGUACCAGGGCGGCGCGUGGUCUACGCCGAGUGACAGAGACGCUCAGGCUGUGUUCUCAGGAUGACCGAGUGGGAGACAGCAGCACCAGCGGUGGCAGAGACCCCAGACAUCAAGCUCUUUGGGAAGUGGAGCACCGAUGAUGUGCAGAUCAAUGACAUUUCCCUGCAGGAUUACAUUGCAGUGAAGGAGAAGUAUGCCAAGUACCUGCCUCACAGUGCAGGGCGGUAUGCCGCCAAACGCUUCCGCAAAGCUCAGUGUCCCAUUGUGGAGCGCCUCACUAACUCCAUGAUGAUGCACGGCCGCAACAACGGCAAGAAGCUCAUGACUGUGCGCAUCGUCAAGCAUGCCUUCGAGAUCAUACACCUGCUCACAGGCGAGAACCCUCUGCAGGUCCUGGUGAACGCCAUCAUCAACAGUGGUCCCCGGGAGGACUCCACACGCAUUGGGCGCGCCGGGACUGUGAGACGACAGGCUGUGGAUGUGUCCCCCCUGCGCCGUGUGAACCAGGCCAUCUGGCUGCUGUGCACAGGCGCUCGUGAGGCUGCCUUCCGGAACAUUAAGACCAUUGCUGAGUGCCUGGCAGAUGAGCUCAUCAAUGCUGCCAAGGGCUCCUCGAACUCCUAUGCCAUUAAGAAGAAGGACGAGCUGGAGCGUGUGGCCAAGUCCAACCGCUGAUUUUCCCAGCUGCUGCCCAAUAAACCUGUCUGCCCUUUGGGGCAGUCCCAGCCA